CUCGAUCCGCCUUCCCCGCGCCGUCCUGGUCACGGCCCCGCGGGGCAGCCAUGCCUGGCCGUCUGCUGCGGGGCCUGUGGCAGCGAUGGCGCCGUUACAAGUACCGCUUCGUUCCCUGGAUCGCACUGAACCUAAGCCACAACCCGAGGACCCUCCGAUAUGUUCCAGAGGAAUCCAAAGACAAAGUUAUCUCAGAUGAAGAUGUCCUAGGAACAUUACUGAAAGUUUUCCAGGCUCUAUUCUUAAAUGAUUUCAAUAAACAAUCAGAAAUCUUGUCUAUGCUUCCAGAAUCUGUUAAAUCAAAAUAUCAAGACCUACUGGCAGUUGAACAUCAAGGGGUGAAACUGCUUGAAAACAGACAUCAACAGCAAAGUACCUUUAAACCAGAAGAAAUUCUUUACAAGACUUUGGGUUUCAGUGUUGCCCAAGCAACUAGCUCAUUGAUUUCUGCUGGAAAAGGUGUCUUCGUUACUAAAGGAUUGGUACCAAAAGGCGCAGUCGUAUCUAUGUAUCCUGGUACAGUAUAUCAGAAGUAUGAGCCGAUCUUUUUCCAGUCCAUUGGAAAUCCGUUUAUUUUUAGAUGCCUGGAUGGGGUACUCAUUGAUGGGAAUGACAAAGGGAUAUCAAAAGUUGUGUACAGAUCUUGCAAUGGGAGGGAUCGACUCGGCCCUUUAAAAAUGAGUGAUAGUACAUGGCUAACGUCAGAAAUUCAUAACCCUCUGGCUGUGGGACAGUAUGUCAACAAUUGUUCCAAUGACAGAGCAGCUAAUGUCUGUUAUCAGGAAUUUGAUGUGCCUGCAGUUUUCCCUAUAGAACUGAAGCAGUAUCUUCCAAACAUUGCCUACAGCUAUGACAAACAAAGGUGACAUGACUGUCUACGUAGAAAACUCCAAAGAAUCAACAAAAAAUCGCCUGUAACUAAUAAGCACUUACAGCAAAGUUUCAGGAGACAAGGUUAAUACACAAAAGUCAACUGCUUUCCUAUAUAACAGCAAUGACGAUUGAAAUUUGAAAUUUAAAACACAAGACCAUUUACAUUAGCACCCCAAAAUUAAAAUACUUGGGUAUAAAUAUAACAAAAUAUAUGCAAAAUCUGUAUGAGAAAAACUACCAAACUCUGAUUAAAGAAAUCAAAGAAGAACUUAACGAAGAAAUAUUCUAUGUUCAUGGAUAAGAAGACACUUCAUUGUUAAGACGUCAGUUCUUCCUAGCUUGAUCUACCGAUUUAGCACAAACCCAAUCAAAAUCCCAGCAAGUUAUUUUGUGGGUAUCAACAAACUAAUUUUAUAUGGAAAGGCAAAAUACCCAGAAUAGCCAACAUAGUAUUACGAAAAGAUAAAAUCAAAGUACUGACAGUCCCCAACUUCAAGAUUUACUAUAAAGCUAUAGUAAUCAAGACAGUAUGGUAUUGGGGGGGUGGGGAAAGACAAAUAGAUUAAAGGAACAGAAGAGAGAGCCCAGAAAUACACCCCACGGGUACAGUCAACUGAUCUUUAACCAAAGAACAAAGGCAAUUCCAUGGAGGAAGAAUGUCUUUUCCACAAAUGAUGCUAGUACAACUGGACAUCCACAUAAAAAAAAAGAGAAAUGAAUCUAGACAUAGACCUUACUCCUUUCAAAAAUUAACUCAAAAUGGAUUAUAGACCUAAAUGUAAAUGCAAAACUAUAAAGCUCUUAGAAGACAACAGUAGAAAAUCUAGGUGACCUUAGGUUUGGCAAUGAUUUUUUUAAAUAAAAUGCUAAAAGUGUGAACAAUCAGAUGAAAUUCUAAGUUGGACAUAAUUAAAAUUAAAAACUUUUACUCUGCAAACACACUGGCAAGGGAAUAAAAAGACAAGCCUCAAAAUGGAAGAAAAUAUUUGCAAAACAUGUAUCUAAUAAAGGACUAGAAUCCAAAAUAUACAAAUAACUCCUUAAACUCAACAAGAAUACAAACCACCCAAUUAAAAUCUGGGCAAAAAAUCUGAAUGAACACCUGAAAAAAAAACACACAAAUGGCAAAUAAGCAUAAGAAAAGAUGGUCAACAUCAUCCUCAUGAGGGAAUUACAAAUUAAAACAAAAAAGAGAUGGCAUUAAAAACUAUUACAGUGGUGAAAUCCAAAACACUGACACCACGAAAUGCUGGUGAAGAUGUAGAGCAAUAGAACUCAUUCAUUACUGCUGGAAAUACUAAAUGGAAGACAGUUUGGCAGUUUCAUGCAAAAUAAACACAUUUUCACCAUUCUAUCCUGUAAUCCUUACUCCUUCGUAUUUGGACAAAUGAAUUGAAAACCUACAUCCACAUAAAAACCUGCACAUGAAUAUUUAUAGCUUUAAUGAUAAUUGCCAAAACUUGGAAGCAACCAAGGUAUCCUCUAACAGGUAAGUGAAUAAAUACACUGGUACAUCCAUAUAAUGGAAUACUAUUCAGUGAUAAAAAAAAGAAUGAGCUAUCAAGCCUCAAAACAAACACAAACAAACAAAAAACCCCAUGGUGAAAACUUAAAUGCAUAUUGCUAAGUCAAAGAAGCCAAUCUGAAAAGGCUGCAUACUGUAUAAUUCCAACUAUAUGACAUUCUGAAAUGGCAACAGUACAGACAAUAAAAAGAUCAAUGGCUGCUAGAAGUUGUUAGGGAGGAGGGGGAAGGGACAGAGGGAAGAAUAAAACAUGAGAUUUUCAGGUCAGUGAAGCUACUCUGUAUGAUACUGUACUGGUGGAUAUGUAUCAUUAUAUAUUUGCCAAAAUCAAUGGAAUGUACAACAUGAAGAGCGAACCUUAAUGUAAACUAUGGACUUUAAUUAAUAAUAAUGUAUCAAUAUUGGCUCAUUAAUUUUAACAAAUGUACCACACUAUUAAUAAUAAAAGAUAUAAUAAUAACUAUAGGAGUGGAAGGGACAUAAGGCAACUCAAUACUUUCUGGUUAACUUUGCUGUAAACCUGAAACUGCUCUAAAAACUAAAGUCCAUUAGCUUUUAUAAAAGCAUAAAAUACUGAGCUACCCACCAAAAUGCUUCAGAACCCUGCCUUCCUUUAGGAUGAAAAGAGGAAAUAAACAGAGCAUAUUUUAAUGAGAAUUAUUCCAAACUAUUCUAAUGAACAUACAUAUGUAUUUUGAAUAGACUUUAGUUUUUAAGAGUAGUUUGAGGUUCACAGCAGAACUGAGCAGAAAGUAGAGAGUUCCUAUAUAUCCUGAAGUUCUACUUUCAACAUCCUACAUUGGAGUAGUGUAUCUGUUAAAAAAAUCAAUGUACCUACACUGACACAUCAACACGCAAAGACCAUGGUUUACAUUAGGGUUUACUCUUGAUGAUGUACAUUCUAUGGGUUUUGACAAAUGUGUAAUUACAUGUCUCUAUCAUUACAGUAUCAUCAUACAGGGUAGUUUCAUUGCCCUGAAAAUGGUCUGUGCUCUGCCUAUUCACUUCUCCCUCCUGCCUCGGCCCUGGCACCAGUGAUCUUUUUAUUGUUUCCAUAGUUUUGCUUUUUUCAGAAUAUCAUAUAUUUGGAAAGCUACAGUAUAGAGUCUUUUCAGAUUGGCUUCCUUCACUUAAUAAUAUGCAUUUAGGAUUUCACAUGUCUCCUUGCGGCUUGUUAGCUCAAUUUUUUUAGUGCUGAAUAAUAGUCCAGUUCUGGAGGUGCCACACUUUGUUUAUCCUUUCACCUCAAAGGACAUACAGGUUCCUUCCAAGUUUUAGCAAUUAUGAUGAAAGCUGCUAUAAACACUUUUGUGUGGACAUAAGUUUUCAACGCAUUUGGGUAAAUGCCAAGGAACAGGAUUAUUUAAUUAUACGGUAAGAGUAUGGUUGGUAUUAUAAGAAACUUCCAAGCUAUCUUCCAACGUGGCCAUACCACUUUGCAUUCCUACAGGCAAUGAAUAAGAGUUCCUGUUGCUUCCCAUCCUUACCAGCAUUUGGUGGUGUUAGAAUAUGUUUCUAGUUGUUUUAGUAACAAUGUUUCUUCCUUCAGCAACAGCUACUCUCACUGCUGAAGAGAAAUUAUUUUGAGGCCACAAACCUCUGAAUGGCUUGAUAAGAAAGGAAAGUCAAGGAGAAAUGAGAGUGAGACUUCCUAAAAAAUACAGUGAGUCCACUUUCUGUGUCAACUGUUUAUGUGAAAAGAUAUGUGAAUAUACUAUCAGCCAUUCCAUAAGCAGGCUGUGGCAUCUCUGAGCAAAUUAGUCAUGUUAGAAUGAUAUCUGAAAUGCUAUAAGGGAACAUUAGUAAGUUGUUCUUUUUUCCUACUUAAGUGACUUAUAAAUUAGUUGCUUACAUUCACUGUAACUAGUAAUUUAUCUGUACUAAUCUGCCUAAUUUACCUUAUUCUUCUGUAUAAGAUGAAAAUCUUUUCCAAAAAGCAUGAGUGCAUGUUCAAAGCUUCGGCAUUCUUCUUCCGUCCAUGCAGUCAUUCCUUCUAAGAAAAAUUUUAAAAUAAAAUUUAUGGGCCCCCAAA